ACACAGGAAGCUGAGCCGGCUUGGGGCCCAGCAUACACAGGCCCCCAGGACCCCUGGGGAGAGGGCCCCGCUGGGCUGGCCCUGCAGGGACCAUGGAAUCCAGAGCUGAGUAAGAGCCACCCCAUCCCUCAUUCUCUGGUACAAGAUUCCCGGGCCAGGCCUGAGCCGGGGCAGAGGGGAGCUGGGGCUGGAGCAGGCCCGGGAGGUGCAGUGACCUGCCAGGGCAGGUGGCUGGAAUCAGAUACUCCAUGGGCCUCCGCUAUGACCUUCACUCUGGGACAGGCCACUCUCGGUCCCCUCCUCUCUCUCUCUCUCUCUCUCUCUAUCCAGCUCCUGUGAUUAUGUCUAUAGCUCUGUGAAUGCAUGUACCCCUCUGAGCUUUGUCCUUGGUAUGUCUGAGUGAUGGCUUCAGGGGGUCCACAGGGCGGAUGAUCAGGGCAGAGGGGAGGCUGGGUGUUGGUAUGAGUGGGUGAUCGUGUGUGACUUGUGUCGGCGUGAGGGUGAAGUGCUGGGGUACCCAUGGUGGGGACUGUGUGUGCAACUGGGCGGGACAGUGUGUGUGCAGCUGAUCUCCCUCUAGAUCUCCCUGUCUCUCUCCUUGAGCCCAAGGCUGCCUCUUCUGCUUGAUAUGGGGGCAGAGGAGGAAAGCAGAGAUUGCAGGGCUUACAGUAAGUACCUAGGUAUCCUGCCCUCCUUUCUCUGAUGAGACAUGUGGGACCAGCCACGAGGGUUCUAUGGGGUCUCACACACAGAGACACACAGCCAGCCCACAAGGAUCCCACGCGGUUACCCAGUGACACUCACAGCUGUACAGGAAAAUAUAGAUGUCAUUCACUUGCUCGGGCACACACACUCACAUCUAUACAAGAAAAUAUAGAUGGCAUGGCUAGAUGCAGUGACUCAAGCCUGUAAUCCCAGCAAUUUGGGAGGCUGAGGCGGGCAGAUCACCUGAGGUCAGGAGUUUGAGAACAGCCUGGCCAGUAUGUGAAACCCUGUCUCUACUAAAAAUAUGAAAAUUAGCUGGGCGUGGUGGCGGGCACCUGUAAUCCCAGCUACAGGGAGGCUGAGGCAGGAGAAUCGCUUGAACCUGUGGGGUGGAGGUUGCAGUGAGCCAAGAUCGUGCCACUGUACUCCAGCCUGGGUGACAAAGCAAAACUCCAUCUCAAAAAAAUAGAUAGAUAGAUAGAUAGAUAGAUAGAUAGAUAGAUAGAUAGAUAGAUAGAUAGGUGGGUGGGUGGAUGGAUAGGUGGGUGGGUGGGUGGAUGGAUGGAUGGAUGGAUAGACAGAGACAGACAGACAGACAGAUAGAUGGAUAUAUAUAUAGAGAGAGAGAGAUGUAAUUCACUUAGCUUGGGACUGCACGGGCUGUCCUUCAUAUCUGUGCAGUCUCAUGCCACAGAUAUAGGAGACAGUCUCAUCUUUUCAGGCAGACAGCAGACAGGAUCACACACACACUGCCUGCUCACAAAAGCCAUGCACUCAGCCACACACAAUCAUACACAGCCACACACACACAGUCACACUUUCUCACUCCAUCCUGUACUUGUGUGUUCAAUUAACACUGCUGCACACACAGCCUCACACAACCACACACUCACAGCCACAAACCCCCAGAGUCAUGCACAUGCCGACGCACCUUGUGGCACAUGCACACACAACCACACUUGUGUGCAAAGUGGCAGACACAACCACACAUGCAUAGAAGCAAGUCUCUGGACCCCUUCUGCAUCCCACAGAGGGGGCUCCCCUGCUGUGUUUGAUUGGUUCUUCGAAGCGGCCUGCCCUGCCUCCCUGCAGGAGGAUCCCCCCAUCCUGCGGCAGUUCCCUCCAGACUUCAGGGACCAGGAAGCUAUGCAGAUGGUGCCUAAAUUCUGCUUCCCUUUUGAUGUGGAAAGGGAGCCCCCCAGCCCCGCCGUGCAGCAUUUCACCUUCGCCCUCACAGACCUUGCCGGCAACCGCAGAUUUGGUUUCUGCCGCCUGCGGGCGGGUACCCAGAGCUGUCUCUGCAUCCUCAGCCACCUGCCUUGGUUCGAGGUGUUUUACAAGCUAUUGAACACAGUGGGAGACCUCCUAGCCCAGGACCAAGUCACCGAGGCAGAGGAACUUCUUCAAAAUCUGUUUCAGCAGUCCCUGUCUGGGCCCCAGGCCUCAGUGGGGCUUGAGCUGGGCAGCGGAGUGACGGUCUCCAGCGGGCAGGGUAUCCCCCCCCCUACCCGGGGGAAUAGCAAGCCGCUUUCCUGCUUCGUGGCCCCGGACUCCGGCCGCCUGCCAUCCAUCCCUGAGAACAGGAACCUAACGGAGCUGGUGGUGGCCGUGACUGACGAGAACAUCGUGGGGCUGUUCGCGGCGCUCCUGGCCGAGAGAAGAGUCCUGCUCACCGCCAGCAAACUCAGCACCCUGACCUCGUGCGUCCACGCGUCCUGCGCGCUCCUGUACCCCAUGCGCUGGGAGCACGUGCUGAUCCCCACGCUGCCCCCACACCUGCUGGACUACUGCUGCGCGCCCAUGCCCUACCUCAUUGGAGUGCACGCCAGUCUCGCCGAGAGAGUACGAGAAAAAGCCCUGGAGGACGUCGUGGUGCUGAACGUGGACGCCAAUACCUUGGAGACGACCUUUAACGACGUGCAGGCGCUGCCUCCAGACGUGGUGUCCCUGCUGAGGCUCCGGCUCAGGAAGGUCGCCCUGGCCCCCGGGGAAGGGGUGUCCCGUCUCUUCCUCAAAGCCCAGGCCCUGCUCUUCGGGGGGUACCGCGACGCACUCGUCUGCAGCCCGGGCCAGCCAGUGACCUUCAGUGAGGAAGUCUUCUUGGCCCAGAAGCCUGGGGCACCUCUGCAGGCCUUCCACCGGCGGGCUGUGCACCUGCAGCUGUUCAAACAGUUCAUCGAAGCCCGGCUGGAGAAGCUCAACAAGGGGGAGGGCUUCUCAGAUCAAUUCGAGCAGGAGAUCACUGGCUGCGGGGCCUCCUCAGGGGCCCUUCGAUCCUAUCAGCUCUGGGCCGACAAUCUAAAGAAAGGUGGUGGCGCCCUCCUGCACUCAGUCAAGGCCAAGACCCAACCAGCCGUCAAGAACAUGUACCGCUCGGCCAAGAGUGGCUUGAAGGGGGUGCAGAGCCUUCUAAUGUAUAAGGAUGGGGACUCUGUCCUGCAGAGGGGGGGCUCUCUGAGGGCCCCAGCCCUCCCCAGCCGCUCAGACCGCCUGCAGCAACGCCUCCCAAUCACUCAGCACUUUGGAAAGAACCGGCCCCUUCGCCCCAGCAGGAGACGCCAGCUGGAAGAGGGAACUUCCGAGCCCCCAGGGGCGGGGACACCCCCACUGAGCCCUGAGGAUGAGGGGUGCCCGUGGGCAGAAGAAGCUCUGGACAGCAGCUUCUUGGGGUCUGGAGAAGAACUGGAUUUGUUGAGCGAGAUUCUGGACAGUCUUAGCAUGGGAGCCAAGAGCGCAGGCAGCCUGAGACCGAGCCAGAGUUUAGACUGCUGUCACAGAGGAGACCUGGACAGCUGCUUCAGCCUGCCCAACAUACCAAGAUGGCAACCAGACGAUAAGAAACUACCAGAGCCGGAGCCCCAGCCCCUUUCCCUGCCAUCCCUGCAAAAUGCCUCGUCUUUGGAUGCCACCAGCUCUUCAAAGGACUCCAGGUCCCAGCUGAUACCCUCAGAGUCCGACCAAGAAGUCACGUCUCCAUCCCAGUCCUCAACAGCUUCUGCAGACCCAAGCAUCUGGGGGGACCCCAAACCCUCUCCUCUCACAGAGCCCCUAAUUCUUCAUCUCACCCCUUCCCACAAGGCAGCUGAAGAUUCUACAGCCCAGGAAAACCCCACUCCCUGGCUCUCCACUGCACCCACUGAGCCCAGCCCUCCAGAAAGCCCCCAAAUUCUGGCCCCCACAAAGCCCAACUUUGAUAUAGCCUGGACGUCCCAGCCCCUUGAUCCUUCCUCAGACCCCAGUUCUCUGGAGGACCCCAGAGCCCGGCCUCCCAAAGCCCUGCUGGCAGAGCGCGCUCACCUCCAGCCACGGGAGGAACCAGGAGCCCUGAAUUCCCCUGCUACACCCACCAGCAACUGUCAAAAGUCCCAGCCCAGCAGCCGGCCCAGAGUCGCUGAUCUUAAGAAGUGCUUUGAGGGUUAAGAAUCAGGGGUCCAAGAGAGACCCCAGUCCCUCAAUAAAGCCACAAGAGCCCAAAAAAGCUGGUUUUUUUCCUGGUGAAUUUCUCUGGUGCCCUCACUCUGCUCGGAAAUCCAUCCCACCCACCUCUGUCCCUCCAAGGGCAGCCUCUCUAACUGGCUCCUAGCAGGGAAUUCCAGGAAGCCUCCUGGUCUUCUAGAAUCCUGGCAACCUUACAAUUCCUCUCGGCAUUUGUCACUUCCAUCUCAGCUAAUGCACCCACCAGCUCAAACACACCAAUAAAGCUUUUGUUACAUCUCA